GCUGCUGCUGUGAUCCAGGACCAGGGCGCACCGGCUCAGCCUCUCACUUGUCAGAGGCCGGGGAAGAGAAGCAAAGCGCAACGGUGUGGUCCAAGCCGGGGCUUCUGCUUCGCCUCUAGGACAUACACGGGACCCCCUAACUUCAGUCCCCCAAACGCGCACCCUCGAAGUCUUGAACUCCAGCCCCGCACAUCCACGCGCGGCACAGGCGCGGCAGGCGGCAGGUCCCGGCCGAAGGCGAUGCGCGCAGGGGGUCGGGCAGCUGGGCUCGGGCGGCGGGAGUAGGGCCCGGCAGGGAGGCAGGGAGGCUGCAGAGUCAGAGUCGCGGGCUGCGCCCUGGGCAGAGGCCGCCCUCGCUCCACGCAACACCUGCUGCUGCCACCGCGCCGCGAUGAGCCGCGUGGUCUCGCUGCUGCUGGGCGCCGCGCUGCUCUGCGGCCACGGAGCCUUCUGCCGCCGCGUGGUCAGCGGCCAAAAGGUGUGUUUUGCUGACUUCAAGCAUCCCUGCUACAAAAUGGCCUACUUCCAUGAACUGUCCAGCCGAGUGAGCUUUCAGGAGGCACGCCUGGCUUGUGAGAGUGAGGGAGGAGUCCUCCUCAGCCUUGAGAAUGAAGCAGAACAGAAGUUAAUAGAGAGCAUGUUGCAAAACCUGACAAAACCCGGGACAGGGAUUUCUGAUGGUGAUUUCUGGAUAGGGCUUUGGAGGAAUGGAGAUGGGCAAACAUCUGGUGCCUGCCCAGAUCUCUACCAGUGGUCUGAUGGAAGCAAUUCCCAGUACCGAAACUGGUACACAGAUGAACCUUCCUGCGGAAGUGAAAAGUGUGUUGUGAUGUAUCACCAACCAACUGCCAAUCCUGGCCUUGGGGGUCCCUACCUUUACCAGUGGAAUGAUGACAGGUGUAACAUGAAGCACAAUUAUAUUUGCAAGUAUGAACCAGAGAUUAAUCCAACAGCCCCUGUAGAAAAGCCUUAUCUUACAAAUCAACCAGGAGACACCCAUCAGAAUGUGGUUGUUACUGAAGCAGGUAUAAUUCCCAAUCUAAUUUAUGUUGUUAUACCAACAAUACCCCUGCUCUUACUGAUACUGGUUGCUUUUGGAACCUGUUGUUUCCAGAUGCUGCAUAAAAGUAAAGGAAGAACAAAAACUAGUCCAAACCAGUCUACACUGUGGAUUUCAAAGAGUACCAGAAAAGAAAGUGGCAUGGAAGUAUAAUAACUCAUUGACUUGGUUCCAGAAUUUUGUAAUUCUGGAUCUGUAUAAGGAAUGGCAUCAGAACAAUAGCUUGGAAUGGCUUGAAAUCACAAAGGAUCUGCAAGAUGAACUGUAAGCUCCCCCUUGAGGCAAAUAUUAAAGUAAUUUUUAUAUGUCUAUUAUUUCAUUUAAAGAAUAUGCUGUGCUAAUAAUGGAGUGAGACAUGCUUAUUUUGCUAAAGGAUGCACCCAAACUUCAAACUUCAAGCAAAUGAAAUGGACAAUGCAGAUAAAGUUGUUAUCAACACGUCGGGAGUAUGUGUGUUAGAAGCAAUUCCUUUUAUUUCUUUCACCUUUCAUAAGUUGUUAUCUAGUCAAUGUAAUGUAUAUUGUAUUGAAAUUUACAGUGUGCAAAAGUAUUUUACCUUUGCAUAAGUGUUUGAUAAAAAUGAACUGUUCUAAUAUUUAUUUUUAUGGCAUCUCAUUUUUCAAUACAUGCUCUUUUGAUUAAAGAAACUUAUUACUGUUGUCAACUGAAUUCACACACACACAAAUAUAGUACCAUAGAAAAAGUUUGUUUUCUCGAAAUAAUUCAUCUUUCAGCUUCUCUGCUUUUGGUCAAUGUCUAGGAAAUCUCUUCAGAAAUAAGAAGCUAUUUCAUUAAGUGUGAUAUAAACCUCCUCAAACAUUUUACUUAGAGGCAAGGAUUGUCUAAUUUCAAUUGUGCAAGACAUGUGCCUUAUAAUUAUUUUUAGCUUAAAAUUAAACAGAUUUUGUAAUAAUGUAACUUUGUUAAUAGGUGCAUAAACACUAAUGCAGUCAAUUUGAACAAAAGAAGUGACAUACACAAUAUAAAUCAUAUGUCUUCACACGUUGCCUAUAUAAUGAGAAGCAGCUCUCUGAGGGUUCUGAAAUCAAUGUGGUCCCUCUCUUGCCCACUAAACAAAGAUGGUUGUUCGGGGUUUGGGAUUGACACUGGAGGCAGAUAGUUGCAAAGUUAGUCUAAGGUUUCCCUAGCUGUAUUUAGCCUCUGACUAUAUUAGUAUACAAAGAGGUCAUGUGGUUGAGACCAGGUGAAUAGUCACUAUCAGUGUGGAGACAAGCACAGCACACAGACAUUUUAGGAAGGAAAGGAACUACGAAAUCGUGUGAAAAUGGGUUGGAACCCAUCAGUGAUCGCAUAUUCAUUGAUGAGGGUUUGCUUGAGAUAGAAAAUGGUGGCUCCUUUCUGUCUUAUCUCCUAGUUUCUUCAAUGCUUACGCCUUGUUCUUCUCAAGAGAAAGUUGUAACUCUCUGGUCUUCAUAUGUCCCUGUGCUCCUUUUAACCAAAUAAAGAGUUCUUGUUUCUGAAGAA